AUGUGCCUGGAUUUGCAGGGUGGCUGCAACAGCGCCUGGCCCAUAGGCAGUACCAUGAAGACUCACAGUGUAGGGCAACAGACGACGCCUGAGCGGCUGAAGAAGGUGGGCUCCCAGGGCCUCCCUGCCCAGGCCUGCUGCCACGGCCAGAACCCAGGGGGGCACCGUGUACCUCGCCAGUGGCCUCAGCACUGCGCCUUGCCUCCAGGAGUCUUGGCUUGUUUGUGUGGAGCUGGGGACUGGGAGAGCAGAGCUUGUGACCUGAGGCCCCCCAGCCUCAGGGUGGAGGUGACCACCCUGGACCAAGGCCUGCCCCAGUUAGUGGCUGAGGACAGACAGGAGUACGUGUGGCAUUCCUGCGGCCCCUUGCUCGGCACCCAGGCACUUCCUCCUGCCCCUCUGCCUCUGGAAGGCCAGCCAUGGCAUGGCCACGGGGGCCUGCCACCUGGCACCUCCCCAACACAAUACAUAAAUGAGUGGGUGUGGCUGUUCCAAGAAAACUGUGUUUACACACACAGGUGCGCCAGGCCUGGCCGUCGAGCCCUGGUUUGCCGGCCUUUGUUCGAGACCAGUGGUUCCCAAAUGUGCACCUGUAUCAGCAUCACCCAGAGCGGGGUCAGAGUCUGGACUCCUGGGCCCCACGCGGAGUUGUUGUCAGGGGCCUGGGCUUUGCAUUUCCACAGGUUCCAGGUGCUGCUGCUGGAGCGGAGGCCACGCUCUGAGCACCCUGCUCUAGAAGAAGAGAUGCAGAAAAGACAGGCAGGGCUGCAGAAAAGCCUGUCCCGCCUGGCAUGCUGGCUUUGCUCCAAUGCCAACCCUUCGGAGAGGCCUUCCCUGGCCACCCUGUUGUAAACAGCACUGCCUGUCUCCGUGUUCCCUGAGUGUUCCUCCAGGCACUGUCACUGCCAGACGCUGGUAUUUUUGUCUACUAUGGCCCCCACCCUGGCUGGUACACUCAGAAGGACGGGCUGCGUCCCCUGUGCCUAGAGAGGCAUCUGGCACAGAGCCAGCCUUCAACAUAUAUUGCAUGAAAGAUUCCGUCCAAGGACGCUGUAGAUGUAGGUGGACGCAGACAAAAGCAAAGCAGGACAGUGGAUUCGUCCAAAGACCGGCAGUGUCUUCAGGUGAAGCUGCAGCGUCGAGUCCUGGUGCUUGCAAGGUUUCAGCAGCAGAAACCUGAUGGGGCUCCUUGCACCUGGGAGAAAAGCCACUCCAGUGAGGAUUAUUGCCAGUGAAGGCUGCCCUGGCCCCAGACAAGUUUUCCUAGAAUUUAUGGUAGCAGGCGGGUUGUUAAAGGAUGAUUCCCGAAAGGGCCAGACAUGGUGCUCACAGGGAUGCAGGGUGAGCAUGCGUCGAAGAGCUUCCCUAGCCCAGGCAGCUGUGAGGACCAGCUCAGAAGAGAAGUCCUGAAACAGACACUUACAGAUGAGGAAUAUUGACAUGAUUGUGCAAAUGGACCUGAAACUGGAUUUUCAGGGGGCUGUGAUGGGCUGGAUUGUCUCCCUUAGAUUCUAAUGUUCAAGUCCCCCACACCCCAGUGUCUUAGAAUGCAACUGUAUUUGGAGGUAGACUUUAAAGAGAUGGUUGAAUUAAAAUGAGGCCCCAAAUUCAA